ACACCAGGUCUUGGAGCAAGAGAACUUGGCAGGCUCUCCCCAUGGCAGUCUUAUUCCUCCUCCUGUUCCUAUGUGGAACUCCCCAGGCUGCAGACAACAUGCAGGCCAUCUAUGUGGCCUUGGGGGAGGCAGUAGAGCUGCCAUGUCCCUCACCACCUACUCUACAUGGGGACGAACACCUGUCAUGGUUCUGCAGCCCUGCAGCAGGCUCCUUCACCACCCUGGUAGCCCAAGUCCAAGUGGGCAGGCCAGCCCCAGACCCUGGAAAACCAGGAAGGGAAUCCAGGCUCAGACUGCUGGGGAACUAUUCUUUGUGGUUGGAGGGAUCCAAAGAGGAAGAUGCCGGGCGGUACUGGUGCGCUGUGCUAGGUCAGCACCACAACUACCAGAACUGGAGGGUGUACGACGUCUUGGUGCUCAAAGGAUCCCAGUUAUCUGCAAGGGCUGCAGAUGGAUCCCCCUGCAAUGUCCUCCUGUGCUCUGUGGUCCCCAGCAGACGCAUGGACUCUGUGACCUGGCAGGAAGGGAAGGGUCCCGUGAGGGGCCGUGUUCAGUCCUUCUGGGGCAGUGAGGCUGCCCUGCUCUUGGUGUGUCCUGGGGAGGGGCUUUCUGAGCCCAGGAGCCGAAGACCAAGAAUCAUCCGCUGCCUCAUGACUCACAACAAAGGGGUCAGCUUUAGCCUGGCAGCCUCCAUCGAUGCUUCUCCUGCCCUCUGUGCCCCUUCCACGGGCUGGGACAUGCCUUGGAUUCUGAUGCUGCUGCUCACAAUGGGCCAGGGAGUUGUCAUCCUGGCCCUCAGCAUCGUGCUCUGGAGGCAGAGGGUCCGUGGGGCUCCAGGCAGAGGAAACCGAAUGCGGUGCUACAACUGUGGUGGAAGCCCCAGCAGUUCUUGCAAAGAGGCCGUGACCACCUGUGGCGAGGGCAGACCCCAGCCAGGCCUGGAACAGAUCAAGCUACCUGGAAACCCCCCAGUGACCUUGAUUCACCAACAUCCAGCCUGCGUCGCAGCCCAUCAUUGCAAUCAAGUGGAGACAGAGUCGGUGGGAGACGUGACUUAUCCAGCCCACAGGGACUGCUACCUGGGAGACCUGUGCAACAGCGCCGUGGCAAGCCAUGUGGCCCCUGCAGGCAUUUUGGCUGCAGCAGCUACCGCCCUGACCUGUCUCUUGCCAGGACUGUGGAGCGGAUAGGGGGAGUAGGAGUAGAGAAGGGAACAAGGGAGCAAGGGAACAAGGGACAUCUGAACAUCUAAUGUGAGAAGAGAAACAUCCUUCUGUGAGUCAUUAAAAUCUAUGAACCACUCUA